AACAUUCGGCGACCGAACGCGGCGGUCGGCAGCGUUCGCGCGGGGGCCUGCGAAGCGCUGCUCGGGGCCGGCACUGCCCGCGGGGAGGACGCGCCGCCGCCGCCACCCAGCGCCGCCGCCGCCGCCGCCUCCAGCCGGGCCGCCGCGCGUCCCGGGGGCCGGCCCCGCGAGCGCAGGAGUAAACACCGCCGGAGUCUUGGAGCCGCUGCAGAAGGGAAUAAAGAGAGAUGCAGGGAUUUGUGAGGUUACGGCGCCCCAGCUGCAAGAUGCACUAGCCGGCUGAACCCGGGAUCGGCUGACUUGUUGGAACCGGAGUGCUCUGCACGGAGAGUGGUGGAUGAGUUGAAGUUGCCUUCCCGGGGCUCAUUUUCCACGCUGCCGAGAGGAAUCCGAGAGGCAAGGCAAUCACUUCGUCUUGCCAUUGAUUGGGUAUCGGGAGCUUUUUUUUUCUCCCCUCUCUCUUUCUUUUCCUCCGUCUUGUUGCAUGCAAGAAAAUUACAGUCCGCUGCUCGCCCGCCCUGGGUGCGAGAUAUUCAGCCCCGCUCUCUCCCGUGCAUUGUGCAACCCAAAGAUGAAAGACCGAAGGGGAGAAAGUUAAAGAAAUCGCCCACAUGCGCUGGAUCAGUCCACGGCUUGGGGAAAGGCAUCCAGAGAAGGUGGGAGCGGAGAGUUUGAAGUCUUUACAGGCGGGAAGAUGGCGGACUGGAGCUGAAAGUGUUGAUUGGGAAACUUGGGUGAUUCUUGUGUUUAUUUACAAUCCUCUUGACCCAGGCAGGACACAUGCAGGCCAAAAAACGCUAUUUCAUCCUGCUCUCAGCUGGCUCUUGUCUCGCCCUUUUGUUUUAUUUCGGAGGCUUGCAGUUUAGGGCAUCGAGGAGCCACAGCCGGAGAGAAGAACACAGCGGUAGGAAUGGCUUGCACCACCCCAGUCCGGAUCAUUUCUGGCCCCGCUUCCCGGACGCUCUGCGCCCCUUCGUUCCUUGGGAUCAAUUGGAAAACGAGGAUUCCAGCGUGCACAUUUCCCCCCGGCAGAAGCGAGAUGCCAACUCCAGCAUCUACAAAGGCAAGAAGUGCCGCAUGGAGUCCUGCUUCGAUUUCACCCUUUGCAAGAAAAACGGCUUCAAAGUCUACGUAUACCCACAGCAAAAAGGGGAGAAAAUCGCCGAAAGUUACCAAAACAUUCUAGCGGCCAUCGAGGGCUCCAGGUUCUACACCUCGGACCCCAGCCAGGCGUGCCUCUUUGUCCUGAGUCUGGAUACUUUAGACAGAGACCAGUUGUCACCUCAGUAUGUGCACAAUUUGAGAUCCAAAGUGCAGAGUCUCCACUUGUGGAACAAUGGUAGGAAUCAUUUAAUUUUUAAUUUAUAUUCCGGCACUUGGCCUGACUACACCGAGGACGUGGGGUUUGACAUCGGCCAGGCGAUGCUGGCCAAAGCCAGCAUCAGUACUGAAAACUUCCGACCCAACUUUGAUGUUUCUAUUCCCCUCUUUUCUAAGGAUCAUCCCAGGACAGGAGGGGAGAGGGGGUUUUUGAAGUUCAACACCAUCCCUCCUCUCAGGAAGUACAUGCUGGUAUUCAAGGGGAAGAGGUACCUGACAGGGAUAGGAUCAGACACCAGGAAUGCCUUAUAUCACGUCCAUAACGGGGAGGACGUUGUGCUCCUCACCACCUGCAAGCAUGGCAAAGACUGGCAAAAGCACAAGGAUUCUCGCUGUGACAGAGACAACACCGAGUAUGAGAAGUAUGAUUAUCGGGAAAUGCUGCACAAUGCCACUUUCUGUCUGGUUCCUCGUGGUCGCAGGCUUGGGUCCUUCAGAUUCCUGGAGGCUUUGCAGGCUGCCUGCGUCCCUGUGAUGCUCAGCAAUGGAUGGGAGUUGCCAUUCUCUGAAGUGAUUAAUUGGAACCAAGCUGCCGUCAUAGGCGAUGAGAGAUUGUUAUUACAGAUUCCUUCUACAAUCAGGUCUAUUCAUCAGGAUAAAAUCCUAGCACUUAGACAGCAGACACAAUUCUUGUGGGAGGCUUAUUUUUCUUCAGUUGAGAAGAUUGUAUUAACUACACUAGAGAUUAUUCAGGACAGAAUAUUCAAGCACAUAUCACGUAACAGUUUAAUAUGGAACAAACAUCCUGGAGGAUUGUUCGUACUACCACAGUAUUCAUCUUAUCUGGGAGAUUUUCCUUACUACUAUGCUAAUUUAGGUUUAAAGCCCCCCUCCAAAUUCACUGCAGUCAUCCAUGCGGUGACCCCCCUGGUCUCUCAGUCCCAGCCAGUGUUGAAGCUUCUCGUGGCUGCAGCCAAGUCCCAGUACUGUGCCCAGAUCAUAGUUCUAUGGAAUUGUGACAAGCCCCUACCAGCCAAACACCGCUGGCCUGCCACUGCUGUGCCUGUCGUCGUCAUUGAAGGAGAGAGCAAGGUUAUGAGCAGCCGUUUUCUGCCCUACGACAACAUCAUCACAGACGCCGUGCUCAGCCUUGACGAGGACACGGUGCUUUCAACAACAGAGGUGGAUUUCGCCUUCACAGUGUGGCAGAGCUUCCCUGAGAGGAUUGUGGGGUACCCCGCGCGCAGCCACUUCUGGGAUAACUCUAAGGAGCGGUGGGGAUACACAUCAAAGUGGACGAACGACUACUCCAUGGUGUUGACAGGAGCUGCUAUUUACCACAAAUAUUAUCACUACCUAUACUCCCAUUACCUGCCAGCCAGCCUGAAGAACAUGGUGGACCAAUUGGCCAAUUGUGAGGACAUUCUCAUGAACUUCCUGGUGUCUGCUGUGACAAAAUUGCCUCCAAUCAAAGUGACCCAGAAGAAGCAGUAUAAGGAGACAAUGAUGGGACAGACUUCUCGGGCUUCCCGUUGGGCUGACCCUGACCACUUUGCCCAGCGACAGAGCUGCAUGAAUACGUUUGCCAGCUGGUUUGGCUACAUGCCGCUGAUCCACUCUCAGAUGAGGCUCGACCCCGUCCUCUUUAAAGACCAGGUCUCUAUUUUGAGGAAGAAAUACCGAGACAUUGAGCGACUUUGAGGAAUCCGGCUGAGUGGGGGAGGGGAAGCAAGAAGGGAUGGGGGUCAAGCUGCUCUCUCUUCCCAGUGCAGAUCCACUCAUCAGCAGAGCCAGAUUGUGCCAACUAUCCAAAAACUUAGAUGAGCAGAAUGACAAAAAAAAAAAGGCCAAUGAGAACUCAACUCCUGGCUCCUGGGACUGCACCAGACUGCUCCAAACUCACCUCACUGGCUUCUGUGUCCCAAGACUAGGUUGUGUACAGUUUAAUUAUGGAACAUUAAAUAAUUAUUUUUGAAAUGAUUGCUAUGCAGGUUUAAACUUUUUUAAUGAUCAAAACUAUUAAAAACCAGAGUUCUUUGUUUAAUCAAAAUUGUGUUGGUUGUGAAUAUUUCAAAGCUGCUAUUCCUUUUCCCACAGACAUCAUUGUCAUGGCCAUGUAGGGUGCCCUGCAGUUUCAAAAGCUCAAACUUCGUGGAAAACACAAUAAGUCACUCUACCCAUUAUCAAGAAAUAACUGAGCAUAAGUUGUAACUUCAUUAUUCAACUUUGCCAGUGCAAAUUGUUUUCCACUUCGAAUCUUCAAAUCCACUUGAACUUUUAUCUCUAAAAUGUCGCUGCAUGAAAGAAAGUAUUACGACUUCCAGGUAGGCAGUUCUAACUGAAAUCUCUAUGUUUGAGAUAGAUAUAUAUGAUAAUCGUUUUUCAUUGGGGGGGUGGGGGGAAUUAGUACCAAGAAAACACUAGUAUAAUUAAGAAAUGUUCAGUUUGCACAAAGAACUAUCCAGAUAACCCACCAGCAUGUUAGUGAGAUGGAAAUACAGACCCACAACAGUAACCCAAUACUUGCAGGGGUUGGGGGCACGGUUAUAGAUUCAACCAUUGACCUAAGUCUGCGUAGCACUGGGAAGAGGCUUUGGUUUAGAAGCCAAGGAAUAAUGAGUAUAUUGGGGAGAACAGAUUAUUUACAAGAUGAACUCUUUAAUGUUUGUGAGAAUCUCAAGUUUCAGAGUUUCUCUUUUGAGAAAGAAAAAGGGGUAAUAAGGUAGAAAUUCACACCAAUGAACAAGAGGAUUGCUGCAAAGUAACUGAGGAGAUGUCUCGCCAUUGGGACCCUAAUGCCAUUUUUGGUCAAACAUUGUUUUGAGCAAGAAUCUGGCAAACAAAAUAAUCAACAACAAAUGUGAAUAUAGUUUCAUUUACUUUUAAUUUUUAAAUCUGUGGAAAAGUUUAGUUGUGCUUCUUGUUAAAAAGAACAUUUCUAUCCCUGAAAAUGCUAUCUUGGGCUUAUGAUUAUUGUUAAACUCCAAGUAUAAACUGAAAAAAAAAACAUAUCCCUAACUCUGUUAUGAAAAAUGGAGACUUCUGAUAUUAAAUGCUUUCUUCUACUUGGAAGAGGCCAGAGAAAACAGGGAAGAGAAAGACAUUAUUGAGUUUGACCAUGUAUUAUGCUGAAUAAACAAUAAGCACUUUAGAGUCCCUCCCUCAAACUCUCAUACAUUUCAUAUUUCUUUUCCAUUUAUUUUCAGUUUUGUUUUAGAAGAAAAGUUCAUCAGAGAAUUUUGUUCUGAUAAUUUCAAGUGGCCAUCUUAGGUCAGUGGAAACCGUAAGUCCAUUGGACUUUACCUCAUCCUUUCUUUGUAGACAUCUGGGAGAGGAAGAGGAGCUUGUAAUGAUAGCACGGGGAUGGUGCUGUAAACAGGAGUGAAAGUGUUUGUGGAAGUCCAGAGAAGUGACUCAACAGGCUACCUAGCUGCAGAACAAGGAGUAGAGCCCACAUAUCCAGAUGGUGUUUUGAGAGGUGCGUAGACAGUGAAAUUCAAUUAAAGAGAGGAUUUUCUCCUCAGCCUCAUGACUCAGAACAGCUCCCUAAAUACCUCUCUCAUCUAAUUGGACCCAUCCAUAGUCCAUUCUCAAACAUGUGACAUUUUCCCCUAAGUAGAUGUGAUUAUCUCUUAGGCAUUUGUUGAAAAAUAAUUCUUAGGUCCAUGGUGCUUGCACUUGUGUCUUUUCUAUAAAAUGUUUGGUCUUACAGGUUUCAUGUCAUUUAAGCUGCACUUCUCAGCAAGUUAAAAGAUUAGCAGUUAAUCUUUAUUCAUUUGGCCUUUGUGAAUUUGUAUUUAAAUUAUUUUUUUCAGGAUUGGCAAAUUAUUCUUGUUUCUCCUUUACCAAAAAAUAAAUGCGAUAUUUUGUUCAAUGACCCCAAAACCAACUUGAAACUUAGGUGGUCAUAUUGGCUUGCAAAGCAAUGUCCCUAAUUGUACCAGUCAGUCACACAAGUGGAUUCAAGGACCUGCUUUGCCAGAUUGACCUGUCACCAAGCUCACAACACAUAUCCUCCACAAACAACAUGUGUUAUGUGAAGAAAAAUGGUAAUUAUAAAUAAGAACAGGAUAUAACACACCUUUCAUCCACUUUAAAUCUCCACAGUUUCAUUUUAUGUCAUUCUCUGAGCAAAUCUCUUUGGGAUGUGAGCUAGCGUGUUCUUCUCCCAUUUGGAAUAUAAGGCUGGGAAUAGAACAAUGCUUAACAAAUCAGUGAAGCUCGACAGUAAUAUGUAAUUUUAAUUCAGUUAGGAAAGAGUUGUAUUGCAUUGCAACAAGUUGACAAAUCAUAGCCAUCUCUGUAGGGUGUCAGGAAUUAUCUCCUGGUCAACUUUAAUGAUAACUAGGGGUCCCUAAGUGGGCUAACAUGUGCUGCAUUGGAGAGAAGCCAAGGGCUGAGAGUACAGUGCCAACCACGUAAUGAAUUGCUUGCAGAAAUUCCAAAGAGGACUCAGCCACUUAUGGAUUUCCACACAGCAUCUUUUCCCAGCUCCACAUUAAGACACAGGAUCUUAAAAGUAAUUUUUUAAAAGCUGGCUGUGUAUUUAUUUAUAUGAAAGUGUUAUAAAUAUCAAAGCUUACAAAUACAUUAAUACAUAUCACCUUUGUUGAAGCUAGCAAAAUGGCUCAAAAUUGAGACUGUAGAGAAAAAUCCAUGAAAUAAUCACGAUAGUCAUACCACAAAAGAUAGCAUAGCUAGGUGGGCCUACCUGGUCGUAUCAACACACUUUCAGAUAGAUGCUUCAAAAAAAAAGGGAAAGCUUGUUACUGGAAUCUUAUGUGCAUUACAGUUUAAUUUCUUCUUGUGACAAAUGGUGCUCAAAGAAGGAUCAAUCCGGUUGCAUCCUUCAAUUUCCCUUUUAGAAUGACUUUUGGUUUUCAUUACAGUAGGCUAUGUUAGCCUUUAUUUUGGUGGUUCUCAAAUACCUGGUGACUUGAAAGAGUAUUAUGCUGGUGGCCUUUCAUAAAGGUUACUGAACUUUAAUCAGGGGUGAGAUGAAUGAAUGUGAAUAGGCCUAUAUACUAUUUUUUUUAAUUAAAAAAAAAAAAAACAGGGCACUUGAUUUAAGAACAAACCUGUUUAAAGGGCAGGAUCAGGGGGAAGACAGCCUUACUAGGUUGGAAUCUGAAUGAGAUUCUUGCUGGACAAGGCUGAAUUAUGGAUGCAAAAGCCAAGCAAACUUCCCAGACCUGGAAGUGUCUUGUGUUCCCUUGGGUCUCUUGAGAUCUCCAGUAUUUAAAAGUAGCAGUUAUUGCCAUGAACUCUCAAAUAAAAAUGCUCCUGCCUCUUACUUGUGAAUAUAAUCAACAUGCAGCCAGUACAUCAGGACCGCAGUUGCUGAAUUCAUUUACCUAGUUCCCCUUUACAGCGACUAUGGACAAGAACCUUUCAGUUGGUUUUGUCAUUCUUGGCCAGAUUUAACCAAGAAAUUUCUUUCACUAUCAGCCUCAUUUUCUCAGGCAUGCUUACAGGGACAAAGUUGUUUUGAGUUGAGUUCUCAGCAAAUAAGCAUUAAUAUCAAACUGUGCUAAACUUGUCUCACUUGGUAUAAGAACUUCAGCAUAAAGAGAUUAGUUUAUCCUUUGACACCAAGUCUUUUUUUUUUCUUUGAGACAGAGUCUUGCCCUGUCACCCAGGCUGGAAUGCAUUGGUGUGAUCUCAGCUCAGUCACUGCAACCUCCGCCUCCCCGGUUCAAGCAAUUCUCCUGCCUCACCCUGCUUAGUAGUUGGGAUUACAGGCAUGUGCUACCACACUGGGCUAAUUUUUGUAUAUUUAUUAGAGACAGGGUUUUGCUAUGUUGGCCAGGCUGGUCUCAAACUCCUGACCUCAGGUGAUCCACCUGCCUCUGCCUCCCAAAGUGCUGAGAUUACAGGUGUAAGCCACUGCGCCUGGCCCCCCUUUUUUUUUUCUUUAAAAAAAAAAAAAAGCUUGGGGGAUUAAGUACCCUAAGAUAGUGGUCUCUCCCAUCAGUUCAAUAAUGCUGUACAGAACCUCUGGAUAAAAAAGCUGUUAUUUACACCAUAAUUGUGAUGAUGGAUUUGACUCCUCAAAACCAUCUCUCCCCUUUUUGCCCUUUCCAAAAAUCAAAGGCUUUUGUCUCCAUGAGUUUUACCUAGUAGGGAUUGUAGUUGUCACUGGUCUAGAGUUCCAAUACAUUUUAUAUCAGGAACCUCAGUGAGCUACCCAGAAUUGGAACUUAACAUGGCCCAGCAACUAGGAGAAGAAGGCAAACCUUGAGAAAGCUGAGCCCUCAGGAUAGCACAGUCUCACCCUUGUUUAAAAUCAAGUCAGGCUAGCCUUUCAGUCACUCUGGUUUUGUAAUGAUUUGCCUUUUAGGCCUCAGGCCAUUUGAUUUCUGCAAUAGUUUUCUGUUCUUCUCCUACAGGAAUACAUCCCUGUCCUUUCGGUUGUAACUAUUACUAAAACUAGGGCUAUGCAAAUGACCUGGUUACCAUGUAAUGAACCUUGUGUACUUAUUUUGAGAGAACAAUAUGUAUAGGAUAUGUUGAGGGGCAGAAAGAAAGACAUCAAAAACUGGAACUAUUUUAGGUGGCAAAUUGUAACGCAAAAAACAAAAGUAUACCUUAUUUUGUAUACGAUGUACACUUGGGACAGAGUUUUCUAAUAUGUUGCCAAUGUUUUUGUAGUGUCACCACAGGUCUUUUCUGAAGUGUUUUUCCCAUUUGUUAUAGAGUAUUAAUGACUUAGCGUAAUUAAGCCCUCAAGUAUGUGUGAGAGAGCGCGUGUGAGAAAAUACAAAGCCAUAGAUAUUGAUUUACUUCACUGACCUGUGUAACUUUAUGUCUGGGUUUCGCCAUCCAAGAUAGAUUGUUUUAUAGAGAGUGUCACCAAAGACUUUUUCCUUCCAAUUUAUAGAAGAAAAAAAAAAGAAAUUAUUAAUAAAUGACAUGACUUUUCA